ACCCUCCUCUCUGGAACGUCUGCCUGGAUUUACCCCAUGGAAUGUGGAUUCCUUAAAUCACCUCAUGAUCCCUCUGCAUAUAUAAGCUCCUUUGAAAGAAAACUGUUUUCUUUCUCCCUUGUUUUGCUGUAUUCUGAAGUCUUUUAUGUCUGGGUUUGGCCUUCUCUGUUAGGCUGAGAACACCCUGGGGGCCAUGGUCUGUUUGCCCAGGUUACUAGAGCUCUUGGCAGGGGAUGUUGGCGGGGGGAUCUGAGAAGGGUGGCAGGAACUCAGCCCCUGGCUUUCUCCAGGAUGGCUUGAGAACUCAUGGAGCUCCUUAGACACCAGGGUUGGAUGGUUUGCCUAAUGUUUACUGAGAAGCCAGUCCCCUUCCUGAUAAUUGAGGGAACUGAGACUGAGGAUGCAGGGCCCCUGUAGACCCUCUGUGAUUUCAUUCUGGUGACCUGGAACCCACACAUUUACUCCUUGGACUUAAACACUGAGGCUACAGAGAAUUUGUAUCUGGGGCAUAGGGCAGGGUGCAUAGCCCAAACCUGCCAGAACUAACAAAGGCUACCAAAGAGCAUGUUAGGAGGGGAAUAUAAGCCUGGUUGCUGCGGACCCCGGGAGCUAGGUCUUCCCACUCCCUGGCCAGACCCACGGCAGUCAGACCUUCUGCAGCUGUUCUCCUAUGAAGGGUUUUAUACACUCCUACUCUUCAAAUUCAAAUUCUCUAAAUAAUACCUACCAUGUAUGGAGGGCUCACUAGGUGCCAGACACUGGGCUAAGCCCUUGCACAUUUCAACACAUCUCAUUCUAACAGCUCUGCAAAGUGGGUAUUAUCCCAUUUUAUAGAAGAGGAAACUGAGGUUCUGAGAAUUUAGUCAACUUUCCUGAAGUUGCACAUCUAGUUUGUGGCACAGAGGGGAUUCCAAGUAAGGUGUGCCUGACCCUAAGACCCGUGCUUUCUGUACCGUACCCCAAUCAUUUCACUUCAUGAUGAACUUGACAAUCGACUGUACCUGAAUUCUGCUUUGUUAUAACUCUCUAGCCUCCACAAACACUCAGUAUCCCCCGCCUCCCCACCCUGCCCCUGUCAGCCUUCUAUUCUUAGUGUGGAUGGUGACCUCUGACUGUGGAGUCAGCAGGUAGCUUUUGGAGUGCCUGUAACUCAAACAAUUUAAUCUGACAUCUCAAUCCUGCCACCCUCCCCUCUGUUGCAAACACACCCUCAACUCCCUUUUCCUGCCUGCCUCUGUCCUCCUCCAGCUCCUGUGAGUUCUAGAGGGUUUCCAAACCUAGGAUAGAGCCAGCAAUUCAUUAGUCUUUGUCCUGUUUCCAAGAAUCCCAAAUAUAUAAGAAUUCCUCAUUGAAAAGCCAAGCAUUCUUGGGGGAAAGUGUGUGUCACCAAGAAAGCACGAUUCCUCACAUUGGGAAAGGGGAUCGUAGUCCAGUCCAGGAAAAUAAGUGUAGAUUUCAGUGCCAGAUGGAAGUGGAUUGGCUCUCCCUGACACCUCCCCUCCCCAGCCACCCACCCCUCACAAACCACAACCGGGGAGCUUGCCUUCCCAGUUCAUCUGAGGGCACUAACCGGAUGACAUUUUCCUCUGGAGAGAGAAGGAAAGAAGAGGCAGAUUGUGUGUGUGUGUGUGUGUGCGUGUGUGUGUGUAUGUAUGUGUACACAGUUCUCCUCACCUACAGGCCACUUUCUGUGCAGUUCCUUUUGGCAUGGACCACUUACUGUUUGAAGAGCCCUCUAGUGAGUUUUUGGGGUGGGGGUGAAUCAUAGGCGAUGAGUCUGGCUGCUCUUCCACUAGGAGGAAGCAUCUCCCUCCUCUUUGGGGCAGCUCAGCUUACCAGAAGAUCUAAGGUAAAUGAAUAGGAAAUCUGCUCGAAAGCAUUUAGAAAGCAACCUCUUAUGGCUGCGUUAUGCAAAUUCAUAGGCUAGAAACAGGACAGGCACCAAGAGGAAGCACGUGAGCUGAGUGAGCAGAGUGUGUGUGGAGUGAGUUAUAAUCAAGAAAAGCUUUAGGAGGAUAUGAAGUUGCUUUUUUUAAAAAAAAUUCUCUCCUUUAUUAUAAAAGAAACAUGGAUUUAUUAUACAAAAUACAUAGUAGCAGAAGACAAAAAUAAAAUUAGUUCAUGAGCCCAUCACGGGGCACUGAAAAGAGACUUUGAUCUUUCUGUUCCUCUGCCCCCUUUCCCACAGCUUCCCACCUGGCCACAAACAACACUUGGAGAAUCUGCCUUCCCAGGUCACUUAACAUUUGGCAGUUAAUGUUUCCAGUCUUUUCUCUCCACAUACAUUGUAAAAGCAUGGUUGAAUACAUAUUAUAUGUGCAGAUGUUAGACAGUUUUGUAUUGUGGUUUUAUCUUCUGGUUAGUAUUACCAACUUUGUAAAUGAGGAGAUAAGUCAAGUGAGGUGUGGAAAAGGGUCAUGGCCACUGUUUGGUAGAGAGGAAACUGAGAACUGGGGGAAAGGGGCCCUAAAAGACCAGCUGAUACCCUGUGGGAUGGAGGAUCUUUUAAAUCAAGCUUGUUCAGCCCGUGGCCCAUGGGCUGCAUGCGGCCCAGGAUGGCUUUGAAUGAGGGCCAACACAAAUUCAUAAAAUUUCUUAAAAUGUUAUGAGAUUUUUGCAAGGUUUUAUUUUUUUUAAGUUUUCUUUUUCUUUCUUUCUUUUUUUUUUUUUCUCGCUCAUCAGCUAUCGUUAGUGCUAGUGUAUUUUAUGUGUGGCCCAAGACAAUUCUUCUUCUUCCAGUGUGGCCCAGGGAAGCCAAAAGAUUAGACACCCUGUUUUAAAUGACAGAAGAUGAAGAGCAUCUAAACCUCAACCUCCCAGCUCCUAUGUGAGUUGGGAGCAGUAACAAAGCCAGCCUCCCCUUUGACCUUGGCUUGGUUUCCCUGGCCACAGAUGGAGCUCUGAUGCCUUUGUUGGGGUUGGCGUUGGCGUUGGGUGAGCACUGUGGUGAGCACUUCACAUACAACUGAUUUUCUGUUUUACAGAUUUGGAAACUAAAGUUUAGAACAGCUAAGGACCUGGAGUAAGAUCCAUGUGGCACAGCAGCAGAGCUGCAAUUCAAACGCGUUCAUCUUUCUCCUAACCACUGUCCUAGGCAGCUUCUAGUUCCAUGGAAGAGAAUGUCUCCUGAUUCCUCACUUUCUGCUAAGCCUUUCUGGAUUGACUCACCAAAGAACAAGGGGUGCCCUCCCACCAUUUCUGUGGAACUCAAAUGCCUGAGCCCUGCUGUAUGGAGUGUGUAUCAAGGAGAUUUGAGGAAAUAAGUAACCUCAGCAUCUGUUCUCACCACGUGGCUCUUCCUCCAGGAAGUUUUCCAGGUUGAAUUCCACUGGAUACUCAUCCCUCUCCUCCUCCAUUCUCUUCAGUAUUAGCCUGAUUCAAUUCAGAGCCACUCAGUCAUUGAUAUUGUGACCAGAUGUCACCCGAGGAGCCCUGUCUUUGAGAUUCAGAAUAAAUUAGCUGAAUCUCACUGCCACAAACAGAGGGCAGUGGUUCUCAAAUUGUGGGACCUUAGACCAGCAGUAUCAGAAUCACCUGUGAACUUCUUAGAAAUGCACAUCCCUGGGCUCUGCCCAAGGCUUCUGGAUCAAGCUCUAGGGGUGCAGCCCAGCGAUUUGUGUCUUAUCAAGCUCACGUGGUGAUCCUGGUGCACACUGAAGCCUGGGAACUGCUGGUCUGGAGAUUCCAAAAUAAGUGGUGGUGGCUUAUAUUUUUCACAUCACCUCUGGCUCUGAGUUCCUAUUUCCACUGAAUUCGUUAAGAUUAUUAACUACCCCUAGGUGACAAGCAUGGUGGCCCAGAAAUUAACAUGAACUCUGGAGCCAGACUGCUGAGAUUUCAAUUCUGUCUCUAAGGCUCACUCAUUGUAUGGGUGUCCCUGAGCAAGUGGCAUAAAUUCCCUCUGCUGCAGACCUCUUAUCCCUAAUAUGAAAUAACCAUGGUAUUCCCCAUAGGGCAGCUGUGAGCCUUCAAUGAAACUGUGUCUGUUAAACACAGUUUAACAGUGCCUUACACAUAGUAAGCUCACAGGAAACAUUAACUCUUAUUGGUGUCAUGCAAACCACGAACUCUUCUGCACUGUGUUGACCCAGAUGUGGAAUUACUCCCAUACCCCUGGUUUACACACACACACACACACACACACACACACACACCGUUUACACAAGGCUUCAUGAAUGCGGUGAACUUUAUGGAGGUCUGGGGAGACCAAGGGUAUUUGUAUUACAACAAUUCAGAAUUGAGCACUGGAUAAGCUUAUUCUAAAAUAGAUUGGCCAAAGGUUACACCAUUUGGUCUUCCUCCUCUCUCCCUUGGUGCUCACAAGCAACUCACUCAAACAGGUCCCCCUCUUUAUUAUGUUGAGUAAUUCAGCUGUCUUUACUCUCCAGCCCCACUCCUCAACUUUGCUCCUCAGUUCACUUUGCAAAUCCAAAGACAACUUCUAAAGAAUGGACCUUCUACCCUGAUUCUCAUGCUGGAUUCCUCCCUCAUAGGGAGAAGAGUAGCAAUGAAGAUUUAUUUUUCCUACUGACAUGAACUGUGCUACCUCUCAGGAUGCUUUAGUGAUAGUUUUGGUUUUUCUCUAUAGGUAUAUGAAUCACACGUUGUAUUUUUUCUAGUAAAUACUUGAGAAAGAAUUUGAUCCAGGAGUCUGGGGCAGAGCCCAAGGCUGCGCAUUUCUAACAUGUUCACAGGUAAUGCUGAUACUGCUUAUCUGAGGUCCCACAGUUUGACUGCAAUGUAUUUAUUUUUGCAAUGGGGCAUAUUGCUCUAUAAAUGUUCUCCUGCUCUUGUUCUAAACCUUCACACCCUCAUAACUAGGGAUUUGAUCACAGCCACAGGUUCUCAAUCUUGAUACUAGGCCACAUAAUUCUUGGUUGUGGGGGGGCUAUCUUUUGUAUAUAGGAGGCUUAUUAACACCCCGAGCCUCUACUCAGUAGAUCUCAGUAACAUUUACUAGUUACGAGAACCACAAAACUUCUCCAGACAUUGCCAAAUGUCUCUGGGGGCAGGGGGUGUGAUGGGUAGCCACCCCCAGUUUUGAGAGCUGCUGGUCUCAGCUAAAUAGUUCCUGUAAUAGUUCAAGUCCAUUAUAUCUUAUUCUACCCCACACUUUACCUCUGUAUUUAAGUUCAGGGGCCUGGAUUUAUUCAUUGAGAAGAAAGGUAUGGAGGAGUCCCAGCAGCCUCUGGAUCACCCUUGAUUUCCAAGGAGAAUCAUCAACACUUUGUGACUGCUUUUUCUCAAAGGCUCCACACUUAACCCAUCUGCAGUGGAGCCAAGGACAUCCAGAUCACAAUGAGGACCUAGGGCAUCUGUCUGCUGACGCCCCCUGGCCUGCAGUGACCAUGGCCCCCCGCAAGAGGAGCCACCAUGGCCUGGGCUUCCUGUGCUGCUUCGGGGGCAGUGACAUCCCCGAAAUCAACCUCCGGGACAACCACCCUCUGCAGUUCAUGGAGUUCUCCAGCCCCAUCCCGAACGCAGAGGAGCUCAACAUCCGCUUUGCAGAGCUGGUGGAUGAAUUGGAUCUCACUGACAAAAACCGAGAGGCUAUGUUUGCACUGCCCCCUGAGAAGAAAUGGCAGAUCUACUGCAGCAAGAAGAAGGAGCAGGAGGACCCCAACAAGCUGGCAACCAGCUGGCCUGACUAUUACAUCGACCGCAUCAAUUCCAUGGCUGCGAUGCAGAGUCUGUACGCGUUUGAUGAGGAGGAGACGGAGAUGAGGAACCAAGUCGUGGAAGACCUGAAGACAGCCCUCCGGACACAGCCUAUGAGGUUUGUGACCCGCUUCAUUGAGCUGGAGGGCUUGACCUGUCUGCUAAAUUUCCUCCGGAGCAUGGACCACGCCACCUGUGAGAGCCGCAUCCACACCUCACUCAUUGGCUGCAUCAAAGCAUUGAUGAACAACUCCCAGGGGCGGGCACAUGUGCUGGCACAGCCUGAGGCCAUUAGUACCAUAGCCCAGAGCCUACGCACAGAGAACAGCAAGACCAAGGUGGCUGUGCUGGAGAUCCUGGGUGCUGUGUGCCUCGUGCCUGGUGGCCACAAGAAGGUGCUGCAGGCCAUGCUGCACUACCAGGUGUAUGCAGCAGAGCGAACCCGCUUCCAGACCCUGCUGAACGAGCUAGACCGAAGUCUGGGCCGGUACCGGGAUGAAGUGAAUCUGAAAACAGCCAUCAUGUCCUUCAUCAAUGCUGUCCUCAAUGCUGGAGCUGGAGAGGAUAAUCUGGAGUUCCGCCUACAUCUACGGUAUGAAUUCCUGAUGCUGGGUAUACAGCCUGUGAUUGACAAGCUCCGGCAACAUGAAAAUGCCAUCCUGGACAAACAUUUAGACUUCUUCGAGAUGGUGCGGAAUGAGGAUGACCUGGAGCUAGCCAGGAGGUUUGACAUGGUCCACAUCGACACCAAGAGUGCUUCCCAGAUGUUUGAGUUGAUCCACAAGAAGCUGAAGUACACGGAGGCCUACCCCUGCCUGCUCUCUGUGCUGCACCACUGCCUGCAGAUGCCCUACAAACGGAACGGUGGCUACUUCCAGCAGUGGCAGCUCCUGGACCGCAUCCUCCAGCAGAUUGUCCUCCAGGAUGAGCGGGGUGUGGACCCUGACCUGGCUCCCUUGGAGAACUUCAAUGUCAAGAACAUCGUCAACAUGCUCAUCAACGAGAAUGAAGUGAAACAGUGGCGAGACCAGGCAGAGAAGUUCCGGAAAGAACACAUGGAGCUUGUGAGCCGUCUGGAGAGGAAGGAGCGGGAAUGCGAGACAAAGACAUUGGAGAAGGAAGAGAUGAUGCGGACGCUGAACAAAAUGAAGGACAAGCUGGCCCGGGAGUCCCAGGAGCUGCGCCAGGCUCGGGGACAAGUGGCAGAGCUGGUAGCCCAGCUCAGUGAACUCUCAACAGGCCCUGUAUCUUCCCCACCACCCCCUGGGGGCCCACUCACCUUGUCUUCCUCAAUGACAACCAAUGACCUGCCUCCACCCCCUCCUCCUCUGCCCUUUGCCUGUUGUCCCCCUCCCCCACCACCACCCCUUCCUCCCGGGGGACCCCCGACUCCCCCAGGUGCCCCACCUUGCCUCGGCAUGGGCCUGCCCCUCCCUCAGGACCCCUACCCCAGCAGUGACGUCCCACUCAGGAAAAAGCGUGUCCCCCAGCCUUCUCACCCACUGAAGUCCUUCAACUGGGUGAAGCUGAAUGAGGAGCGUGUCCCUGGCACCGUAUGGAAUGAGAUUGAUGACAUGCAGGUAUUUCGGAUCCUGGACCUAGAGGAUUUUGAAAAGAUGUUUUCAGCCUACCAGAGGCACCAGAAAGAGCUGGGCUCCACUGAAGACAUCUACCUGGCUUCCCGCAAGGUCAAAGAGCUGUCGGUCAUUGAUGGCCGGAGGGCCCAAAACUGCAUCAUCCUUCUUUCCAAGUUGAAGCUUUCUAACGAGGAGAUCCGGCAGGCCAUCUUGAAGAUGGAUGAGCAGGAGGACCUUGCUAAGGACAUGCUGGAGCAGCUCCUCAAGUUCAUCCCAGAGAAGAGUGACAUUGACCUCCUGGAGGAGCACAAGCAUGAAAUUGAGCGGAUGGCCCGUGCUGACCGCUUCCUCUAUGAAAUGAGCAGGAUUGACCACUACCAGCAGCGACUGCAAGCCCUCUUCUUCAAGAAGAAAUUCCAGGAGCGGCUGGCUGAGGCAAAGCCCAAAGUGGAAGCCAUCCUGUUGGCCUCCCGGGAGCUGGUCCGCAGCAAGCGUCUUAGACAGAUGCUAGAGGUCAUCCUAGCCAUAGGCAACUUCAUGAACAAAGGGCAGCGUGGGGGCGCCUACGGGUUCCGGGUGGCCAGCCUCAACAAGAUCGCUGACACCAAGUCCAGCAUCGACAGAAACAUCUCUCUGCUCCAUUACCUGAUCAUGAUCCUGGAGAAGCAUUUUCCUGAUAUUCUAAACAUGCCUUCAGAGCUGCAACAUCUUCCAGAAGCUGCCAAAGUCAACCUAGCAGAACUGGAGAAGGAGGUGGGCAACCUCAGGAGGGGCCUGAGAGCGGUGGAGGUGGAGCUGGAGUAUCAGAGGCGCCAGGUACGGGAGCCCAGUGACAAGUUUGUCCCUGUCAUGAGCGACUUCAUCACGGUGUCCAGCUUCAGCUUCUCCGAGCUGGAGGACCAGCUAAAUGAGGCCAGGGACAAGUUCGCCAAGGCCUUGAUGCACUUCGGGGAGCAUGACAGCAAGAUGCAGCCAGACGAAUUCUUUGGCAUCUUUGAUACCUUCUUGCAGGCCUUCUCAGAGGCCCGGCAGGAUCUAGAGGCCAUGAGGAGGAGGAAGGAGGAGGAGGAGCGGCGGGCGCGCAUGGAAGCCAUGCUGAAGGAGCAGAGGGAACGUGAGCGGUGGCAGCGGCAGCGGAAGGUCCUGGCUGCAGGCAGCUCGCUGGAGGAGGGAGGAGAGUUCGAUGACCUGGUGUCGGCCCUGCGCUCUGGGGAGGUCUUCGACAAGGACUUAUGCAAGCUCAAGCGCAGCCGCAAGCGAUCAGGGAGCCAGGCCCUGGAAGUUACCCGGGAGCGGGCAAUAAACCGGCUAAAUUAUUGACCUGGGGAACUAGCCACACAGGAGGCCGGGAGACAGGGACUGGUGAGAAUGGGGCUGAGUGGAGGAGGUGGUGAUAUUUAAACCAUUUGGUGCUUGGUUUAGAGCCUUGGGCUGGGUCCUGGGAUGGGGGGCUGUGUGUGGCUGGACCAGGUGUCUCCCCACGCUUACCUUAAGGGGCUCCUCUUAUCUCCCCUUCACAUGAUUCCUUCUGUGCCCUGGCCCCAGGUAUUAUUCUGAGGCUGCCUUGGAUGGCCUCAGGCCAGGUAACCCCAGGCUGAAGGGGCCCUGCUCCCCAUCCCCUACCAUGGGCACCCAUGUGCUGGCACAGAACAGUUCCAGAUCUAGACUGGAGAGGUCCACAGCCUUGUCCAGAGUUCCUGUGUAGCACGGGGAGCAAUGAUGGAGGGAGCCCCUGAGAGGGAAUCUGGUGAGGGAAUCCAGACUCCCUUCUCUCAAGGGGAGGCUCAACAGAACAUUGACCUGGGGGCAAACUUUCCUCUUGAAUGGGAACAGAGGAGGCAUUAUAUAUUCUAGUUAGAUCAGCUCUGGUAGGUUCCAGAGAACAGUCAAUGUUGGAAGGAUGAUGCAGGGACCAAAGCCAUCAGGACAGAGUAGCAGUGUCUGUUUCCCAUGUCACAAGUCCUCUGGCCUCUCCCUGCAUGUCUUAAGUAUCUUUCCCUUCCUUCUCUACCCUCACCUCCAUCCUGUCUACUAAUCCACAGUCCUAGAAGACUCACCUUGGGUUUCCACAGCUAUGGCUCACUACCAGGUGCUUGAUGAAUCUGGCGAGGGGCUCAAGACAGACCUCAUGCAUCACCACACCUCAUGCCUUUUGGGCAUCUCCCAUGUCCCCAUCUCCUGGACACCUGGCCAUUGUUGUGAAGCCAGACAGUGACCUCAAAUGUUGCCUUGGAGUCCCCUACAGCCCCUCAGCAGAGGGCAGCACUUGAAUGCUUAGCUCCAUCCCAUAGUUCUCUACUUCAUAUAAAUUGCUCAGGCCCUCCCACCCCUUCUCUAACACUAGCUUCAAGGCAGAAGCCACAGCAGCCUCUGUCCAGCCUGCAGGUGGCCACUUGGAACCAUGUGUCCACUGGCGUUGGGGAGUUGGUUCCUGAGAGGUCUGAGGGCCAGAGCUGCCCUCUACAUUAACAUGCUGUCUCUAAGGGUGGCCCCUCCUCUCAGGCGUUCAGAUGGUGCGAACAGCAGAGCAGGCAAGGGAAACUGGGGAGAUGGGGAUGGAGGAGGAAGGCUGAUAUCCUCUGGGGAGCACAUCACCUGAAGGUGCCAAGGAGGAAGGCUGAGAGGGGGGCCACCCCAUUUCUGGUACCCAAUUUGGUUCUUCAGCCCAACUUGCAAGGGGUUCCUUCUGGUCCUCCCAUCCACUGCCACCUUCCAUUUUGUCCAUCUCAUGCUGGCCUUGGUGGAUGGGAUGGCUGUAUCUAGACAAAAUUUUUCUAAAACUCCAUCAAGGCUCUUAUUCAAUACCACGUUCCGAGUUGGCCUUUCAUCUUCUUUGAGACUGGCCCUGCCUAACCUCUACCAUCAAUGAGCUCUUGGCCCUUCUGCCCUUCCCUGUGUUUCUCACUUUCCAACCUAAUCCCUGGCUCAGGGUUAUUGCCAGUGGAGACUGGUGAGCUGGGCCUACUCUCAGCUGCCUAUCUUCUGCCUUUCACUUGCAUCCAACUCCUGGGGCUGGGACCGUAGUAGCUGCGGGGGGGAAGAAACACAGGGUCGGUGAGCCCAGCAUGUGCGUUGGUUUGAGGGGGCGGGCGGUGUGUGUGUGUUCUGGUGGGAGGGAUCUGAGCAAGUGCAAGCCUGGCUGACACAGGUGUGAAGAGGCCAUCCUGGAACCCAGGUGAGGGCAAGAUGAAGGCUUCCAGGCAGAACAGCUGCAGAGAGUUUGGCUAUAUGCAUCUGCAGCCCCAAGAGCUCCCACUGCAAGACAAGUGUUGGGGAAGAUGGGAGGUUGUGGGUGAGGCCUCUAAAGGUCCUCUCCCAAACUGACCAGGCUGAUGUCAACCUAACCCCCUCAGGGGCAGGGAACAGGGGAGGGCUCCACAAGCGUGUCUGGCAUUCCCACCCACCAUGGAAGACUGGAUACGCACCUGGAAACAAAAGGACUAUGGAAGCUGUUCAAGAUACAUUUGAUCUUCAGAAAAGCAGAAUUUGGUUCAACUGUUGACAGAGGACACAAAUACGUUGUUCCAGAGCUCAGCCUUCUCACUCUAAAAGAAAGAUAUUUUUCUAUUUAUUUUCUACAUCUGGCCAGUGGCUCUGGUGCUAGAUGCCACUGUAGCCAGAUCUCCAACAGUGCCUUGGACCAUGGACUCAUACUCAACUGAGUAAGAAGGGGCUGGUGCCCAGUCGGGGUGGCUGAGCUGGUCCUUAAUAGGUUGUUUCUUGGUCUUGCUUUCUUCAUGCCCUCCCCACUGCUCCUGCCACCUUUAGAUAAGUUUCUCUAGCUAAUUUUGUGGCCAAUGUAAAAUUCGUCAUCAACCUAACAAACACAACCUUCUCAGCAGCAUUUCUCCCCUGUGAUGGAAAUAAAGUGUUUAGGGCAGUGGGAGGAGAAAAUUCUCCAGGUGAAUGGGGAAGGGUCUGUUCCAGCCUCUCCCUACUCCCAUCCCAUUUCCACCAACUGGGGAACUGUGACUAUCUAUCUCCCCCGACUUCUACCAGGGAUGCCUUCACGCCAAGGCUGUUCUCACCAGCUGCCUCAGAUGACAAAUGAGGCUAAUGGACAUAAUCUACAGUGUCCUUUUUCACUUGCACCUUUUUUAUAAGAAUAUAUUGUAAUACUAAAAAAUAUUAAAUUCAUACCAUCCCUACCCA